GACAGGAAGGAGCCGGUCCAGGCUCCGGGGGCUGGGAAAGGGCGCGUCUCAAAGGCUGGCUGGAGUGGAGCCAAGGGAAAAGAUCGUUAGAGACAGCGCCCCUGACCAACCACUUAGAGCAGCGCAGGGGUGGGAGGGCGGCCGCAGGCUCUCCUCUCGUUAGUGCCCCCUGUGUUUGGGGCCCCGUGAUCUCAACGGUCCUGCCCUCGGUCUCCCUCUUCCCCCGCCCCGCCCUGGGCCAGGUGUUCGAAUCCCGACUCCAGAACUGGCGGCGUCCCAGUCCCGCGGGCGUGGAGCGCCGGAGGACCCGCCCUCGGGCUCAUGGCGGCCCCGGUCCGCCUGGGCCGGAAGCGCCCGCUGCCUGCCUGUCCCAACCCGCUCUUCGUUCGCUGGCUGACCGAGUGGCGGGACGAGGCGACCCGCAGCAGGCGCCGCACGCGCUUCGUAUUUCAGAAGGCGCUGCGUUCCCUCCGACGGUACCCACUGCCGCUGCGCAGCGGGAAGGAAGCUAAGAUCCUACAGCACUUCGGAGACGGGCUCUGCCGGAUGCUGGACGAGCGGCUGCAGCGGCACCGAACAUCGGGCGGUGACCAUGCCCCGGACUCACCAUCUGGAGAGAACAGUCCAGCCCCGCAGGGGCGACUUGCGGAAGUCCAGGACUCUUCCAUGCCAGUUCCUGCCCAGCCCAAAGCGGGAGGCUCUGGCAGCUACUGGCCAGCUCGGCACUCAGGAGCCCGAGUGAUACUGCUGGUGCUCUACCGGGAGCACCUGAAUCCUAAUGGUCACCACUUCUUAACCAAGGAGGAGCUGCUGCAGAGGUGUGCUCAGAAGUCCCCCAGGGUAGCCCCUGGGAGUGCUCGACCCUGGCCAGCCCUCCGCUCCCUCCUUCACAGGAACCUGGUCCUCAGGACACACCAGCCAGCCAGGUACUCAUUGACCCCAGAGGGCCUGGAGCUGGCCCAGAAGUUGGCCGAGUCAGAAGGCCUGAGCUUGCUGAAUGUGGGCAUCGGGCCCAAGGAGCCCCCUGGGGAGGAGACAGCAGUGCCAGGAGCAGCUUCAGCAGAGCUUGCCAGUGAAGCAGGGGUCCAGCAGCAGCCACUGGAGCUGAGGCCUGGAGAGUACAGGGUGCUGUUGUGUGUGGACAUUGGCGAGACCCGGGGGGGCGGGCACAGGCCGGAGCUGCUCCGAGAGCUACAGCGGCUGCACGUGACCCACACGGUGCGCAAGCUGCACGUUGGAGAUUUUGUGUGGGUGGCCCAGGAGACCAAUCCUAGAGACCCAGCAGCAAACCCUGGGGAGUUGGUACUGGAUCACAUUGUGGAGCGCAAGCGACUGGAUGACCUUUGCAGCAGCAUCAUCGACGGCCGCUUCCGGGAGCAGAAGUUCCGGCUGAAGCGCUGUGGUCUGGAGCGCCGGGUAUACCUGGUGGAAGAGCAUGGUUCCGUCCACAACCUCAGCCUUCCUGAGAGCACACUGCUGCAGGCUGUCACCAACACUCAGGUCAUUGAUGGCUUUUUUGUGAAGCGCACAGCAGACAUUAAGGAGUCAGCCGCCUACCUGGCCCUCUUGACGCGGGGCCUGCAGAGACUCUACCAGGGCCACACCCUACGCAGCCGCCCCUGGGGAACCCCUGGGAACCCUGAAUCAGGGGCCAUGACCUCUCCAAACCCUCUCUGCUCACUCCUCACCUUCAGUGACUUCAACGCAGGAGCCAUCAAGAAUAAGGCCCAGUCGGUGCGAGAAGUGUUUGCCCGGCAGCUGAUGCAGGUGCGCGGAGUGAGUGGGGAGAAGGCAGCAGCCCUGGUGGAUCGAUACAGCACCCCUGCCAGCCUCCUGGCCGCCUAUGAUGCCUGUGCCACCCCCAAGGAACAAGAGACACUGCUGAGCACCAUUAAGUGUGGGCGUCUACAGAGGAAUCUGGGGCCUGCUCUGAGCAGGACCUUAUCCCAGCUCUACUGCAGCUACGGCCCCUUGACCUGAGCUUAUGCCGUGAAACAGCCCCCAGCCCCCGUCUGUCCCCCAACCCAGGCUAGCCAGCCUUUUAACAACAUCUUUUGGGGUACAAUUAGAAUCUAAGUGUUUGCAGCCAUAUGUGUCAUGUAGAAGAUGCCUAGCCCUGGGGACCUUGUGAAAUACGCAGGAACCAGGGAUACCAUCUGGUCCAGUGGUUUUUAAACAAAGCUGCUUAGCACCUGGAAUUCCCUGGUCAGGGAGAUGGAGUCAGUGGGGCAUUGCAGCUUGGAAUCUAUUUUAUGUCACCAGUUGGUCCUCAUCAAAUAAAAUUUCCUUAGGAGUGCAGAGGGCUCAUUGGGAAAAUAAAAAUAAUAAAAAUAAAUAAAACUUCCUAAAAGAAAAGAUUGAAAACCA